AGAGCGGCAGCCUUUUCCCGCGCGUGCUGCCUUCGCCGCUCGGGCCGCCCGGGGGAAAACAUGGCGUCUGCCCUGGAGCAGUUCGUGAACAGUGUCCGACAGCUCUCAGCUCAAGUGUUGUUCCUGUUUUCCAGGGCAAAUGACACAGCUUUGUGAACUGAUCAACAAGAGUGGGGAACUCCUUGCGAAGAACUUAUCCCAUCUGGACACUGUGCUCGGGGCUCUGGAUGUACAAGAACACUCCUUGGGCGUCCUUGCUGUUUUGUUUGUGAAGUUUUCUAUGCCCAGUGUUCCUGACUUCGAAACGCUAUUCUCACAGGUUCAGCUCUUCAUCAGCACUUGUAAUGGGGAGCACAUUCGAUAUGCAACAGACACUUUUGCUGGGCUUUGCCAUCAGCUAACAAAUGCACUUGUGGAAAGAAAACAGUGACAACAUAAGAUCCAAUGUGCUGCCAUCUUUGAGAACUUAUCUGAAAGAGAUGUCAUUUCUGACAGCCCCUGCGAGGAAUUGGCAUCCUUAAGCAAGCCAUAGACAAGAUGCAGAUGAAUACAAACCAGCUGACCUCAAUACAUGCUGAUCUCUGCCAGCUUUGUUUGCUAGCAAAAUGCUUUAAGCCUGCCCUUCCAUAUCUUGACGUGGAUAUGAUGGAUAUCUGUAAAGAGAAUGGAGCCUAUGAUGCAAAACACUUUUUAUGUUACUAUUAUUAUGGAGGGAUGAUCUAUACUGGGCUGAAGAACUUUGAAAGAGCUCUCUACUUUUAUGAACAGGCUAUAACUACUCCUGCCAUGGCGGUCAGUCAUAUCAUGUUGGAAUCAUAUAAAAAGUAUAUUUUAGUGUCUUUGAUAUUACUUGGCAAAGUACAACAGCUACCAAAAUAUACAUCUCAAAUUGUGGGUAGAUUCAUUAAGCCUCUUAGCAAUGCAUACCACGAGUUAGCACAAGUGUAUUCAACCAACAACCCCUCAGAACUCCGAAACCUGGUGAAUAAGCACAGUGAAACCUUCACUCGCGAUAACAACAUGGGGCUGGUGAAGCAAUGCUUGUCAUCUCUUUAUAAGAAGAAUAUUCAGAGGCUAACAAAGACCUUUUUAACUCUAUCAUUACAAGAUAUGGCAAGUCGUGUGCAGUUGUCUGGACCUCAGGAGGCAGAGAAAUACGUUCUGCACAUGAUAGAAGAUGGUGAGAUUUUUGCAAGUAUUAACCAGAAGGACGGUAUGGUCAGUUUCCAUGAUAACCCUGAAAAAUAUAAUAACCCAGCCAUGCUUCAUAACAUUGAUCAGGAGAUGCUGAAGUGCAUUGAGCUGGAUGAGCGGCUGAAAGCCAUGGACCAGGAGAUCACAGUGAACCCUCAGUUUGUACAAAAGAGUAUGGGCUCACAAGAAGAUGAUUCAGGAAACAAACCAUCCAGUUAUUCUUGAAACUAACAUCCAUCCUGAGCUAAACAAGAGAAACUACCAUCUUGGCCAGUGACAAGUGUUCGGAGGGCAGCAGAGAGGACCAAGCCUGUGUCACCUGGAGACUAAGAAAUUAAGUUUUGUUUUGACAUCUUCAGUCCUGUGUGCUUUCAGAAAACCAUUUUCUCUGCAAAGAAAGGAAACAGAUUUGCAAACUUUAAAGUCUGUCGUGGAUUUAUUUAUCCUCAGAUUAUUGUUACUGCAUUAAAUCUACCUUUUUGUUUUAAGUUGCUUGAACAUUAAUGUGUCUUCUGUAUCACUUUUUUCUCCUCUGAAGUUUUUAAUAAGCACAUUCAUUGUGAACAGAAAUAGCUGGAUUUUAGGAAUUUUUGGAAGAUUUGGAUCUGAAAGGUUUUUAUUUAUUGACAAAUUUGUAUCUACAAAAAAAUCUAAAAGUUGUAAUCAUUGUCUUCAGAAAAUAAAAGAAAAGAAAGGCCAGACAGACA